AACGCCACGCUUCCGCCUUCUGGAAGCCUGCACUCCAGCUUCGAGUGUGAGAGACCCGUCCCGGUGGGAGGGACCUGGGCUGGGGGGGACGGUAGGGGAACAAGGGCGUGGGACUGGGGAAGCUUCUGGGAACAUUUGCUCUAGGUAUUCAGCUAAACUAAGAAAAAUUGGUCCAAGGCUCGGCACAAAAGGAUCUUCUCAUUCCAGUCCUUUCGCCCACGCAGGGAACGAUGCCUCUGGAGGUGGUGGUGGAGCUGCAGAUCCGGGCGAUUUCUUGCCCAGGAGUGUUCCUGCCUGGCAAACAAGAUGUGUACCUCGGGGUCUACCUCAUGAAUCAGUACCUGGAGACCAACAGCUUUCCCUCUGCGUUCCCCAUUAUGAUUCAGGAGAGCAUGAGAUUUGAAAAGGUAUUUGAAAGUGCAGUAGAUCCUGGAGCUGUAGUAGACCUUUUGGAAAGCUUCCUAGCCAGGUUUGAAUUAAUACAGCUAGUUCCUCCAGUGUGGGAUGAGUUGGCCUACUACGAAGAAAACACACGAGAUUUUCUUUUCCCAGAGCCCAAGCUGACACCUUCGCACCCUAGGAGGUGUAGGGAGGUGCUCAUGAAGACGGCUCUGGGUUUUCCAGGCAUUGCUCCCAAAAUAGAGUUUUCUACAAGGACAGCCAUCAGAGAAUGUGUGUUUCUGCAUAGAAACAGAUUUCUUGUUGAUUCCAAAUCUUGGCUAUUGUGAAUAGUGCUGCAGUAAACAUGGGGCCACCUUUCUUUUGCUGAGGCUGAUGCUCGGAUUGUAUUCAUGGUCCGUCUUUGGGCUGGGGAAACAAAGGGAAGAUGUUGGUUCAGCAAGAACACAGAAGCUUAAAGAAGAAACUGAACAGAAAUGGGACCCAGACCUCUGGAGAAGGGCUGCUUUCCUGGAUGCUUCUUCAGGAAUUCGAAGGAAGAAAGACAUGAGUCACGGAGGCCUUUAUCUACAUCACAUGAACCAAUAUUUCCCUUAAAUACUAUAAAGAUGAAACUAAAGGAGAAUAAUCUCAACAGACUGCCCAAAGGCAUGCAAGCCCGGGCGCCCUCUCAAUAUUCUACCAGGCAUUUCUUCCAGGACCAGCCAGCUCAGUUGAACCUUGGAAAUAAUUUCAAAAUCUCUGGAGGAAGCAAGCCUCCAUUUGUUGUUAGACACGUGGACAGUGCAAAGCCCUUUGGUGAGAAUAUUUCAGAGCAUCAUUUGAGGAGGUCUAGAAGAAAAUCUAAGUUUUCAGACUUUCCGUUUCCAACGAGAAGAGCUUCUUCUCUUGACAGCCUUGCAGCUAACGUAAAGGUUAUCAAAGAGCCAGAUGAACGGAUUGUUUUAAGGAGUGACUCAUCAUCAUGUUUAGAUUCAAGUCAGUUUGGAAAGUCUUCAUCCAGUAAACAAGGGGAUGCUGAUUUCCACGGGAAAGCUUCAUUUGCCACCUACCAGCAUUCCACCUCUCCUGGCCCCUUGGAUCAGCCCCUUCUCAGAGAAAGGUUCCAUCCUGGUUCUCAGUCCACAUGGAAGAAUAUCCAUGAGAGGGUAUGCAGUCUUCUGACAUCCCACAGAGCACAGCUGCACCAAAACAAGGAAGAUUCUACCUCUGAAGUAAAUUAUAUCAUUGAAAGACCAAGCUACCCUCUGAAGAAAUACUCACUGCAUGAACAGAGAUAUUUUUAAGGGGAAAUUAAUGAAAGCUUAAGGAGAAUCAUGAAGAGCUCACUCACUGAGACAAUUGAAGCAUCCUUAAAGAAAUGAACACUUUUUGUUGUCUGUGUUGAGUCACUGAUGUCUAAUCCCCUUUAAACCAAACCCUGUACUCAGUCUUUUGUGCCCAGGUAAGAGUUGUUGAUUAAAGUGUUUGCUGUUUGGGGGCUAACAUUUUCUUGUCAAGCUGGAAAAUUUGUGUUUUUGCAUGUUUGUUUUGAACAUGAAAGAGAAAGCGCUGUAGUUGGGUGGCAGGUGCUUAUCUGAACACUUCCCCUCUCUCUCUCUCUGGCUCUCUCUGGCUCUCUCUGUCUCUCUCUCUCAAAUUAAUUAUAUAUGAGCUAGAGGAAGUUGCUAUUCACAGGAAUAACCUGAUAAAUCCUCCAGGAAAGACUAUCAACCUGACUUUCUCUUUUCGGUAGAUCCGUUUUUGUUGUUGUUUGUUUAUUUCUUAGUGUUAGGCUUGAUUUACGUGAAGUCCACUAAAAACCUUGGAAAAGAGAGCAUUACGUCUGGGUAGUUCAGAUCUUGUUUUAGAUGUUGAAUGUCUGUGAUAAAUUUGUAAGAGGAGGCUGGCUCCUCUGGAGCGUAGUUUAAACUGCUCCUUCUGUUUCCUACUCCUUCGUUCCAGCAAUUCUUUGUAAAUUUAGAUGAGGAACAAAACCUUCCUCAAAUAUUUCUCCAAAAGAACUACACAUUAAGUAAAUAGGUUCUACAGAUAGGACUGCCAAUGCCAGGUUUUAAAGUUAGUUAGGAAGGUGCAUCUAUGAAAUGCUUACACAGUGUGAGGGAGCAGGAAUAGGAAGGGGCUGGGAUAAAGGGAGACUAGAGGCACAUUUGUCUUCAUUGAUACAGACCCAGAGAAGAGGGGCCUGAAAAUGGAAACUUAUUUCCCUCCUUCAUAGUGUAAGCAUAGCAUUUUCCUCUACCAGCCCUACUAUAGUGUGAAUGUUUGUGUCCCCUCAACAUUUGUAUGUUGAAAUCCUAACCUCUAAGGAAAUGGGGCCUUUUGGGAGGUGAUGAGGUUGUGAGGGUGGACCCCUCAUAAAUGAGAUUAGUGCCCUAUAAAUAGGCUCAAGGGAGCUCGUUUGCCCCUUCCACUGGCGAGGAGACAGCGAGAAGGCGCCAUCUCUGACCCAGGAAGAGGGCCCUCACCAGAUUCUGCAUCUGCCAACAUUCUGAUCUUGGACUUCCCAGCUUCCAGAACUGUGAGAAAUGAAUUCCUGUAGUUUGUAAGCUACCCAGUUUAUGACAUUUUGUUAUAGCAGCCUGAAUAGAGUAAGACACUACCCUAAAACUUGUUCAGUUUUUAGAAGAUUCAGUGAGAGCCAAGUUUUCUUUUCUCACUGUAAUCAUAGGGAUUGGUUCAUUAGGUAAAUUAAGAAAAUGAAAUUAAAAAUUAAAACAGAAAAGGAACUCCAAAAACAAAAACAACAAAACAAAAUUCAUUUAUCCUCUUCUUAGAAUUUCAGCCAAAUAAAGGUAUAUCCAAGUUGAACCUCCCAAUCUAAAAAUCUGAAAUCUGAAAUGCUCCAAAAUCCAAAACUUUUUGAGCACCAAUAUAACACCAUAAGUGAAAAAUUCCACAUCUGACUGCAUGUGGCAGGGUGCAGUCAAAUGCAUUCGAAACUUUGUUUCAUGCUCCAAAUUAUUUAAAAUCAUGUAUAAAAUUACCUUCAGGCUACCUGUAUAAAGUGUAUAUAAAACGUAAAUGAAUUUCGUGUUUAGACUUGGGUCCUAUCCCCUAUCCUGAAGAUACUUCAUUGUGUUUAUGUAAAUAUUCCAAAAUACAAAAACAAAAACCAAAACCCAAGUUUAAAAUACUUCUGGUCAGUCCCAAGCACUGAAGAUAAGGGAGACUCAACCUGUAUCACAACCAGCAUUCCACCUUGGCAAGGCCAACAGCAAGCUUAAAUUACAUAUGCUAAUAUGUUCUCAGUCUCUCUGAAACUAUGGUUGUCAAUUUGUUGUUUUGAUGUUACCUCUAAGUAGUCAUCAAAAGUAAGAAAAUAUUGUGUUACAUUAAGGUUACGCUAUAAGUCUCAGGAGAGGGCUGCUUACGUAAGCAGCUAAAGGAAAGCAGCACUAAUGAAUUGGUAUCCCAUUUCAGUUAUUGUUAAAAUAUACACCAUGACAUUCAAUAUUCAGUGUUUUUUGAAAUGGUUUAAGCAUAACUCUUUAAUAAGAUCUUAAAUGCCCAUUCUUAUUUAAAGUCAUUUUUGGUUUUCACACUAAAUUACGCUUUUUUUCCCUUUACUUUUGCAUCUAUUAACUCUAUUCCUUAAAUUAUUAUUAUUUUUACUUUUGUUUCUCAAGGAGUUAUCUCAAUUUUGAGGAAUCAUGCUGGGGCAAGGAUUGCAGUUGAAGUAUUUUGCUUUUGGAGUGUAUAAUAGUAUGAAUAAUUUUGUGAUGUUUUGGGGUUUGGAUUACUUUGGGAAGAUCUGUGUCAUUAAACAUCAUAAAAAGAA